CUUGUUUCCUGAGUUGUCCUGUGCUGGAGGUCUGCUCAGACGAAGGUCUCCAUGGCGUUAGAAGUCUUGAUGCUCCUCGCUGUCUUGAUUUGGACCGGUGCUGAGAACCUCCAUGUGAAAAUAAGUUGCUCUCUGGACUGGUUGAUGGUCUCAGUUAUCCCAGUUGCAGAAAGCAGAAAUCUGUAUAUAUUUGCGGAUGAAUUACAUCUGGGAAUGGGCUGCCCUGCAAAUCGGAUACAUACAUAUGUAUAUGAGUUUAUAUAUCUUGUUCGUGAUUGUGGCAUCAGGACAAGGGUAGUUUCUGAGGAAACUCUCCUUUUUCAAACCGAGCUGUACUUUACCCCAAGGAAUAUAGAUCAUGACCCUCAGGAAAUCCAUUUGGAGUGUUCCACCUCUAGGAAAUCAGUGUGGCUUACACCAGUUUCUACUGAGAAUGAAAUAAAAUUGGAUCCUAGUCCUUUUAUUGCUGACUUUCAGACAACAGCAGAAGAGUUAGGAUUAUUAUCUUCUAGUCCAAACUUGCUCUGAGCUAAAGGAGAAAUGGAAACUUGAAGCUGGUGUUAUGUAUUUUGCAGGAAAACAGUUUCAUUUUUUCAUAGCAAAAAUAUAGUUGGUGUAUAUCUCUCCUUAAGUCUCUGGUUUCUAAAAACCCUACUUCAGUAAAGGUCCUGAUUAGUUGAUUAGUGAAUGUGUAUUUCUAAAUAUUUGUAUUCAGUAGGGGUAUGGCUGAUUAAUUUAACAUUAACUAUUAGGUAAUUCAUAUUAUACAUUUAAGUUCUUUCUGUUCUGUGUAGAAGAUUCAGAAAUAUGUCUUCAAAGACAAUGACUUGAUCUAAUUGAUAAGAACCUCCAAUAAAUAUGUUCUAAUAUUUUUCAGGAAGAAUAAAGAAUAGAGAGAGACAUAUAAAUGUGCAAGAGGCAAAACUUUGAGCAUAGUGUAAAAUUUAACAUAUUAACUCUCACGAAAGGCAAAAUCCUUUUAUGUGCAGAUACUUUAAUUCAUGUAGAUUUUCCUAUUAAUCAGUAAAGUUGAAUCCUAACAAUAAUGCCAUGUGACAACCUAUUUAGAUUAUUCCAGAAUUAAAUUCAAUUUAUUUUCUAGAGCUCAAGUAACCACUACCUUAACUGAAAUUUGAUGUUAGGUUUCCCUUGUUCCUCCGAAUGGUUCUUCCACACUCAAAAUAAUUGAAUGGUUGAGUUGGUUAAGCAAAGAGUUAUCCUGCCACCUAAGAGCAUUCAUUAAAUGAUUAUUUAUUACCACCUACUUUAUACUAUCUUCCUUUCUUUAAACAUGGAGUCUAAAUAUGUAAUAUAUCAAAAAAUACUUCUGAUUUGGUAGAUUUCUUAUAUCAAGGGUGAGAAUUGAACUGUGCCAUUGGCUAUUCAAUAGCUUAUUGAAUGUAUGUUUUGGAUGCCACAUCCUCCUGGAAGCAAAUUUUGCCAAGAUACUGUUUAUUAUUAUUUUUAAUUAAAGUGAUACUAUUCCAUUUUCAAUUAAA